CAUAGGAAAAUAUAAACAUUGAUGAAGCCUCCAGAUGCCUGGUGAAACACAUACUUGCAAAUGAGUGUGACCUAAUGGAGUCUAUUGAGCCGGACGUCGUGAAGCCCCAUCUCACAUCAACCAAGGUUGCCAGCUGCUCUGGCUGUGCCAAAUCCUAGUAGGCACCUUUGCUGGUGUCUGGUAGGAAUGACCUCAUUGUUCCACAAAUUGUGCCUCUAUUUUUACCAUUUUGGGUAAACGUCAGGAUAGAGAUACCACAUGUGGCAAGCCAAAGAUCUAUGCCUCUGUUUUUUCAGUGAGAGAGAAAUAGCAAAUGUUCUUUCUAUGCUUUCCUCACCAUCAUCACAGUGUUUACAAACUUUUGAAAAUAUUUAGUCUGUUACAAACUUCUGUCAUGUAGCUGACCAAAAUCCUGCAGGGCCACAGUCGGCACUGUUAUUUGCUUCUUUUAAUCAGCAAAGGCCUCAAGUCUUAAAAUAAAAGGGGAGAAGAACAAACUAGCUGUCAAGUCAAGGACUGGCUUUCACCUUGCCCUGGUGUCUUUUUCCAGAUUUCAGUAUAUUCUCUGAUGGCCUGACAGGCCUAUUAAGUAGAUGUGAUAUUUUCUCCCAAGAUGACCUCCAUUCUCGGCAGACCUAAGAGUUGCCUCUGAGUUAGCUCUUUGGAAUCGUGAACACAGGUGUGCUAUAUUGUCCUUGUCCUAACUGUCACUUGCCAUGGCCUGAAUGUUGGCUUAACUGAAUAUUGUAUGAAAAGACAUGCCUCCAUAUGUGCCUUUCUGUUAGCUUUCUCUGACUCAAGCUGUGGGGCUCCUCUAUACAUGCUAUACAUGUAAUAUAUAUUAUAUAUAUUUUUGCAAGUGAACAAUAAAACAUUAAAAGAUGCUGUUUCCCUA